CCCUUUCUCCUGCAGCCAUGGAUGCCGCUCUGCUCCUGAACGUGGAAGGGGUCAAGAAAACCAUUCUGCACGGGGGCACGGGCGAGCUCCCAAACUUCAUCACCGGAUCCCGAGUGAGUGGGGCCCCUCCGGAGCAGACAGGGUCCCCCACAGCAGCUUUCAACAUUCCAGGUGAUCUUUCAUUUCCGCACCAUGAAAUGUGAUGAGGAGCGGACAGUCAUUGACGACAGUCGGCAGGUGGGCCAGCCCAUGCACAUCAUCAUCGGAAACAUGUUCAAGCUCGAGGUCUGGGAGAUCCUGCUUACCUCCAUGCGGGUGCACGAGGUGGCCGAGUUCUGGUGCGACACCAUCCACACGGGGGUCUACCCCAUCCUAUCCCGGAGCCUGAGGCAGAUGGCCCAGGGCAAGGACCCCACAGAGUGGCACGUGCACACGUGCGGGCUGGCCAACAUGUUCGCCUACCACACGCUGGGCUACGAGGACCUGGACGAGCUGCAGAAGGAGCCUCAGCCUCUGGUCUUUGUGAUCGAGCUGCUGCAGGUUGAUGCCCCGAGUGAUUACCAGAGGGAGACCUGGAACCUGAGCAAUCAUGAGAAGAUGAAGGCGGUGCCCGUCCUCCACGGAGAGGGAAAUCGGCUCUUCAAGCUGGGCCGCUACGAGGAGGCCUCUUCCAAGUACCAGGAGGCCAUCAUCUGCCUAAGGAACCUGCAGACCAAGGAGAAGCCAUGGGAGGUGCAGUGGCUGAAGCUGGAGAAGAUGAUCAAUACUCUGAUCCUCAACUACUGCCAGUGCCUGCUGAAGAAGGAGGAGUACUAUGAGGUGCUGGAGCACACCAGUGAUAUUCUCCGGCACCACCCAGGCAUCGUGAAGGCCUACUACGUGCGUGCCCGGGCUCACGCAGAGGUGUGGAAUGAGGCCGAGGCCAAGGCGGACCUCCAGAAAGUGCUGGAGCUGGAGCCGUCCAUGCAGAAGGCGGUGCGCAGGGAGCUGAGGCUGCUGGAGAACCGCAUGGCGGAGAAGCAGGAGGAGGAGCGGCUGCGCUGCCGGAACAUGCUGAGCCAGGGUGCCACGCAGCCUCCCGCAGAGCCACCCACAGAGCCACCCGCACAGUCAUCCACAGAGCCACCUGCAGAGCCACCCACAGCACCAUCUGCAGAGCUGUCCGCAGGGCCCCCUGCAGAGCCAGCCACAGAGCCACCCCCGUCCCCAGGGCACUCGCUGCAGCACUGAGCCCCCUGAGGCCCACAGCCACCCAGGCAGGGAGCAAGUGGCCUGGUCACUUCUGGUUCGAUUGACCAGGAUCGUGGUGUCACUUUUUAAAAUUUAAAAUUAAUUUUUGAAAUCAAAGUCAGACACACCCAUGGUAAAAAAAAAAAAAAAAACAAUCCCAAGGGUACAGAAGAGCUUAUGAAUAAAAGUAGUUUUCUCCUCUACCCCUCUCAUUCCUUCCGUGCCAUGGUUUUAAUUGACCCUGUUUUUAAUUCUUCUGGUAGUUUUCUCUAUUUCCAAGUAAUCUGUUUAAAUCAGUUUCUAGAUUUUACCCCAUGUCAAUGACAAAUGAGGAUUUGAUGCUCUGAUCCUUUCUCAUGCCUGAUACCCCUCCCUGUCUCCCCAUUUUGGAUAGUUACAUUUGGGGGUCAUCUCGGUGAUUUUUGUAACUUUACGCAGGACACUUAGAGCUCUCUAGAAUCCCACUGACUUUAGUGGGUCUUGAUGUAGGGUGGGCAAGCCCCGACACUGGAGCUUAGCCUGAGAGGGUUCUUGGCCUCCCCCAGGAAAGAUUUCAAAGGCAAGCGCCAGUGGUAGGGUAGAAGAAAACAGCUGUGGUCGGGCACGGUGGCUCACGCCUAUAAUCCCAGCACUUUGGGAGGCCGAGGCGGGUGGAUCACCUGAGGUCAGGAGUUCCAGACCAGCCUGGCCAACAUGGUGAAACCUCAUCUCUACUAAAAAUACAAAAAAACUAGCUGGGCGUGGUGGCGGGCGCCUAUAAUCCCAGCUACUUGGGAGGCUGAGGCAGGAGAAUUGAUUGAACCUGGGAGGCGGAGGUUGCAGUGAGCCAAGAUCACGUCAUUGCACUCCAGCCUGGUCAACAAGAGUAAAACUUCAUCUCAAAAAACAAAACAAAACAAAAACAACAACAAAAAACAAAAGAAAAACAAACAAAACCAAAACCAAAACAGCUGUAUUGAAGCUGCAGUGUUGCAGCUCUGUGACUGCCCUGCAGAGCAGGGCUACCCCAUAGGCAGCGAGCAGCAGCUCAGGGCAGUUCUGCAGUCAGAUUUAUACCCACUUUUAAUUACAUGUAGAUUAAGGAGCUGCAUAUACAAAGAUUUCUAGGGAAGGAGUAGUAACUUCUGGGUCCUGGGGUCUUUGCCACGGAACAGGGCAGUAUGCCAGGGUGUUGCCACGGCAAUGGUAAACUGACAUGGCACCCUGGGGGUCAUGCCUUAGGGAAAGCCGCUUCCACUCGCCCCUGUUUUAGCUCAUCUUCAAGUUAGUCUGGUGUCCAAGCUCCACCGCCUGCCUCAGUCUGGUGACCUCCUUCUGUGUCUGAUGAGCAUGGCAGCGUUGGGACCUUCCCCUUCCAACUCUCUCCCUCCUCUUCGUCCUCCCUAAAGGACGGGUACGAGGAGGGGCUAUCACGCCAGCGACAUCCUCUAGCACCACCCAGGUGUGUGGGGUGGGGCAGGGGGGCGACGAAGUAUCCAGCCCAGGGCCACGUAGUCAACUGCCAAGGGCUUCCUGGGCUUCUCUUCUGCCCCAGAGCUUGUCUCCACCCAGCAGGGGUUCCCCCAGCGCUAACUGUAUCCCUAAAGUUCUGAUGUACUUUACUUUUCCAUCUUCCUUGUUGUUAACAUCUACCUUCUGCUCUGUAAGCAAAACUAAAUCUUCUGUGCUUUGUCCAUAGGUUGAUUCUACAAUCUGAAAAUCAAUAAACAGCAUUUGCAUGAU